AUUAUUUUCUAAAUUCUGUGCUAACAGAACCGGCUUCAGCUGAAGAAAGAGAGGAAUGAAGCGCCUUCUGCUUCUGUUUUUGUUCUUUAUAACAUUUUCUUCUGCAUUUCCCUUAGUCCGGAUGACGGAAAAUGAAGAAAAUAUGCAACUGGCUCAGGCAUAUCUCAACCAGUUCUACUCUCUUGAAAUAGAAGGGAAUCAUCUUGUUCAAAGCAAGAAUAGGAGUCUCAUAGAUGACAAAAUUCGGGAAAUGCAAGCAUUUUUUGGAUUGACAGUGACUGGAAAACUGGACUCAAACACCCUUGAGAUCAUGAAGACACCCAGGUGUGGGGUGCCUGAUGUGGGCCAGUAUGGCUACACCCUCCCUGGGUGGAGAAAAUACAACCUCACCUACAGAAUAAUAAACUAUACUCCGGAUAUGGCACGAGCUGCUGUGGAUGAGGCUAUCCAAGAAGGUUUAGAAGUGUGGAGCAAAGUCACUCCACUAAAAUUCACCAAGAUUUCAAAGGGGAUUGCAGACAUCAUGAUUGCCUUUAGGACUCGAGUCCAUGGUCGGUGUCCUCGCUAUUUUGAUGGUCCCUUGGGAGUGCUUGGCCAUGCCUUUCCUCCUGGUCCGGGUCUGGGUGGUGACACUCAUUUUGAUGAGGAUGAAAACUGGACCAAGGAUGGAGCAGGAUUCAACUUGUUUCUUGUGGCUGCUCAUGAAUUUGGUCAUGCACUGGGGCUCUCUCACUCCAAUGAUCAAACAGCCUUGAUGUUCCCAAAUUAUGUCUCCCUGGAUCCCAGAAAAUACCCACUUUCUCAGGAUGAUAUCAAUGGAAUCCAGUCCAUCUAUGGAGGUCUGCCUAAGGAACCUGCUAAGCCAAAGGAACCCACUAUACCCCAUGCCUGUGACCCUGACUUGACUUUUGACGCUAUCACAACUUUCCGCAGAGAAGUAAUGUUCUUUAAAGGCAGGCACCUAUGGAGGAUCUAUUAUGAUAUCACGGAUGUUGAGUUUGAAUUAAUUGCUUCAUUCUGGCCAUCUCUGCCAGCUGAUCUGCAAGCUGCAUACGAGAACCCCAGAGAUAAGAUUCUGGUUUUUAAAGAUGAAAACUUCUGGAUGAUCAGAGGAUAUGCUGUCUUGCCAGAUUAUCCCAAAUCCAUCCAUACAUUAGGUUUUCCAGGACGUGUGAAGAAAAUAGAUGCAGCCGUCUGUGAUAAGACCACAAGAAAAACCUACUUCUUUGUGGGCAUUUGGUGCUGGAGGUUUGAUGAAAUGACCCAAACCAUGGACAAAGGGUUCCCGCAGAGAGUGGUAAAACACUUUCCUGGAAUCAGUAUCCGUGUUGAUGCUGCUUUCCAGUACAAAGGAUUCUUCUUUUUCAGCCGUGGAUCAAAGCAAUUUGAAUACGACAUUAAGACAAAGAAUAUUACCCGAAUCAUGAGAACUAAUACUUGGUUUCAAUGCAAAGAACCAAAGAACUCCUCAUUUGGUUUUGAUAUCAACAAGGAAAAAGCACAUUCAGGAGGCAUAAAGAUAUUGUAUCAUAAGAGUUUAAGCUUGUUUAUUUUUGGUAUUGUUCAUUUGCUGAAAAACACUUCUAUUUAUCAAUAAAUUCAUAGACCUAAAAUAAACCUCAACAGGUCUUUUAAUAUAAAUUCUGCUUCAAAAUAGAAUAAAACCAUUCUUUAACAACAAGUUGCUGGUCCUAGUUCUAAAUAUCCAAAUUCAAUGGCCAUUUUGAGCUGCCUGAUUCUUUUAAUAGGAAGUUAUUAUGUAGAAACAAAAAUCUCUGACUGUACUUUAAGCCUAUUUCAUGCUUUGUGGACUUGGAGAAGACAUGUCUUAUAACUGAAUACUGAAACAUUUAUUAAACCAAUCUUUAGCAUUCUA